ACUGAGAAACCUUUGGGACAAUUCAAGAGGAGGAAUGACUGGAGGACAACAGCAGAAAUGUGAAGAAAAUCAGACUGACAGGGUUGAGUGGCUAUUAACACUCUUUCUUUAAAGGAUACAGACCCAGGAUGAAGUCAGAUGUGAGAUUUCCUCUCCAAUUGAGGGUAUGUUUGCAGCCCCUACCUAUUAUAGAUUUUGGAAAGAUAAUCAUCUACACUAAUAACCUGAAAAUCAUUCGAACCCCAAUGGACAAGAGAGAUUUUGUGAGGAAAAUUCUCCAGAAGGAAGAGGAGGCUGAGGAAGAGUCUCUGAUGAACAAAGAAGAAAGCUAUGGAGGCAGGGACCAGCACGAUAGACCUUUGGUGGAGGCAGAAAGCACAUUACCCCAAAACCGGUAUACACAGGAAGGGGAUAUUCCCGAGGACAGCUGUUUUCACUGCCGAGGGUCGGGCAGUGCCACCUGCUCUCUGUGCCACGGCAGCAAGUUCUCGAUGCUGGCCAACAGAUUUAAGGAGUCCUAUCGGGCCCUGAGGUGCCCUGCCUGCAAUGAGAAUGGCCUACAGCCUUGCCAGAUUUGCAAUCAAUAGCCCGUGGCUUUUGCAUGUCCACUGUUAUCUUACCCUCCCUAAAGUUAUUUCUAAUAAACCGCCCCCUUCUCCUCCUCCUGCCUCUCCCAACAAGGAGGCCACAGUGGCUGCAGUCACUCCCACUGCUGGCAAAACUCAAUUAUCUGAUGACAUUUUGUGAGGCCGGUAACAUCUCUCUGUGGGUCUAAGUGGCAGGGGCAUUUCUGAAUUAUAGUCUGCUUUGAAACUGGUUCUAAAAUUAUCCUUCCAGGAUGGUGUGAGUGUAUCUCACUUGACUUAGCUCAGUUUUCUUCUUGCUUCAGUGAGCAAAUACAUGUACACUUCAGGCAUCAGGUUGGGAGUUAUUUUGCAAAAUUAUGUGGUGAGAAAGGAGUAAAAAAGGCAGGUUUCUGAUGAACUGAUUUCUUGUUGCUUAUAAUGCAUCUCAUGUGAUUAUUAGUCAAACUGAAUUUCUGAUUAAGCAGAAGAGGAAACGGACAGCCAACGCUGAACGCACUAGCAGGCCACAGCAAGCAAAAUGGGAUGUUCACUGUGGAGACAGGCAAGCCAAGGAGCCUUCCCUUUCAAAGUCCUGAACCUCUUCCAUGUGGUGUGUUUGGAUAAUAUUUAUGCAGACAGUGAGCAAUACUAUUUCUUAAGUCAAGAUGAGAUAAGACAUUUUUGUGUGCCUCUAACUACUGAGGUUAUAAGCCAAGUCAAAGUUAUUUAUGAUAAAUUUGGUGCUCAAAUAUGUGUGUAUGAUAUAACUUCUUCGAGCCCCUGAAUUACUACCAAAUAAAUAAAUCCACUUUAAGUCUAGAACCUAGCCAUGAUCUCUUCAUAAAGGACUGCAGGUAUUUUAUAGAUUACCUACUGGAAAUCUCUAAAAGAAAAAAAUUAACCAAGGCUGAUUUUUAGCAGUAAUGUUUCUACUAUCCAUGAAUAUGCAUAGUAAGGAUGAUUCUUUCCUCUUGAGGUUGGUUAUAAAAUUAGAACAUACUUUUGUUAAUGAACUUUUAUAGCUCUAACACCCACUCCCCAAGCCCCUUAAGAAUAACACUGCAAAAUUUAUCUCUUGAGACCUGCUGCAUUCUGUGAUAAUAAUUUUGAUUUCAUAACUUAAUAAUUUCUCAAGAUUUGUUUGUUAUUCUCUAAUAUUCAGCGUUUAACAUAAUUUAACAAUGGAAUGCUUUUCAGGCAAUAUAAAUAAUUCUAAUAAAAAAGACUAAAAUAUUUUUGAAGCCUUGAUAGUUUUGCCUGUCCUUUCAUACUCAGGAGUUACCAUAUUGCUCACCAGCUUUCUUUGCUUCUGUCCUUAACUGUUAUACCUCCUGCCUCUGUUUAUGUUUUCUCACAGCUGUUGGCUCUUCUGACUUUUCAGAAUACUAGAGGAAGGAGGGAUGUUGAGAGUGUAUUCUGCUUUUUUUUUUUUUUUUUGUGGGAGACAGAGUCCGCUCUGUUGCUCAGGCUGGAGUGCAGUGGUGCAAUCUUUGUUCAUUGCAACCUCUGCCUCCCGGCUUCCAGCGAUUCUCCUGCCUCCGCCUCCUGAGUAGCUGGGAUCACAGGCACAUGCCACCACUCCCAGCUAAUUUUUGUAUUUUUAGUAGAGACGGGGUUUCGUCAUGUUGGCCAGGCUGGUCUCCAACUCCUGACCUCAGGUGAUCCGCCCAUCUCGGCCUCCCAAAGUGCUGGGAUUACAGGCAUGAGCCACCGCGCCUGGCUCUAUUCUGCUUUUCGACAGGAAUAUUCCGUCACAAAUAUUGUUUGAGCCCCGCUGCAUACAGGACAGUAUUCCAAAGUGCUUGAUGUAUCAUGUUACCCAGAGAGGCAUCAUCCCUUUGGUAUCUCAUGGAACUUAGUUUUAGAGGAGGAGAUAGAUACAUAAAUGGAUAAUUGCAAUGCACUGUGACAAGUGCUGGGAUAGGAUAAUUACAGGGAGCAUUUGGAGCAUGCAGAAGGGGCAUCUAAUUUAAGCCUUAGUGGGGUUAUGCAGGUUGCCCAGAGGAAGAAGUGUGAGCAACCUCAGCUUCUGUAAAGAGCCUUUAAUGUUUUUCAUCACAUAAUAAAUAACCUACUAAUGAUCA